GUAAUCACUAAAUUUUAACUAAUACUAUCUUUGCUUCCAGUAGUGUUCUAUGAGUAUAAUUUUAUCAACAUGUAAAUAUGUGAGGCAUUGAUUCUCAUAAUAAUUCUAUAUGCUAGGUACUUAAAGCAUCCCCAUUUUCCAAAUGUAGGAAACAGGCAAAAAGAAGGUAAAUACUUGGCCAGAUUACUCCUGUAAUCCCAGCACUUUGGGAGGCCAAGGCAGGCAGAUGGCUUGAGCUCAGGAGUUUGGAACCAGCCUGGGCAACAUUGUGAAACCCCAUCUCUACUAAAAAUGCACAAAAAGAACUAAUUUAAGUUUCUUGUAGGAUUCUGGUUAUAAAACACUGGUCAAACACACAGGGCAUGGAUAGGGCAGGGCCAGGGACAAGGUCAGGCCAGGAAGGGGCCAGGGCCAAGGCAGGGCCAGAGCUGGACUUGGAGGUGUCCUGGUCUGAUUUGCCCUGCCCCAACGUUGGCCCAGCCCUGCUCUGGCACGUCCUGUCAUGUCCUGUCCCUGGCCUGAGCAUUGGCCCUGGCCCUGUCCUGCUUCUGGCCCUGCCCCGGAGUUGACCAGGCACUGCCAUGGCCCAGUCCUGCAUUGCCCUGCCCUCCUCUGCCCUGGUGCUACCAUGGCCCUGCUUGGGCCCUAGCUCUGCCUCGACUCUGGACCUGCCCUGACUCUGCUCAGCCCUGGAUCUACCCUGACUCUGCCUUGGUGUUGCCCUCCCAUCUCUAUGGCCUGGCUCUGGCCAUGCCUUGCACAGACCAUGCUCUGCCCUGCGUGCCCCAGCCUGGGUCCAGCCCUCAUCCUACCAUAUUCCUGACCCCAGCCAUACCCUUGUUCUCGCCAUGACCCUGCCGUGGCCCUCUCCUGGCCCUUCCUUGAUCCUGCCCUGCCCUUCCAUGCCCUGGCCUUGCCCUCACCCUGCAUUGGCCCUGCACUGGUCCUGCCCUGCCCUGGCACUGCCUUGGCCCCGGCCCUGCCUUCUUCCUGGCCUUGCCUUUGCCCUGCCCUGGCCUGACCCCAGGCCUACUGAGUCCAUGAAAUGGCCCUGGACCUGCCUUGCCAUCCUCUGUCCUGGCCCUAUAUUGUCCCCACCAUGCUCUGGUCCAGCGCUUGCCCUAGCCCUGUUGCUAGUCCUGCCACUGCUAUGGCCCUGCUCUGUUUUUGGCCGUGCCCUGUGCUACCCUAGCCCUGCCCUGCCUUGGCCUUGGCCCUACCAUGGCCUUCUCUUACCCUGGCCUGGCCCUACCCUGGCCUUUUCUACCCUGGCCUUGCCCUUCCCUGGUCUUGCCCUGCCCUGGCCUUGUCCUGCCAUGGCCCUGGCCCUGCCAUGUCCCUGCCCUGGCCCUGGUUCUUCCCUGCUUCUGGACCUGGCCUUGGUCCUCUCAUGUCCCUGGCUGUGACCCUGCCCCUGGUUUUUCUCUGGCCAUGACCCUGCCCCAGUUCUGUCCUAUCCCUGGCCCUGUCUCAGUUCUGUCCUAGCCCUGGCCUUUCACAGUACUUUAUGCUUAGUAAGGGCUCCAUGGUGUCUGUGAGUUGAAUGUUGUGUUCAUAGUAUCUGCCAAAACAGAAAGAAAAAAGUAAAAUAUUUUGAUAAGAAGUUAAAGCUUUGUAUAUAAUAUGCCUUGAAUUGUAAGUGCCUGUUAUUAGUUGUAUUACAUAUGGGUCAUGGCUUUGUACACGUAACUCCAAACCAUUGAUACUGUUAAAAGGAUAUAUGAAUAUAUGAAAGAAUGUAUAAACGUAAGAAUGUAUCAGUAUCUAAUGACCUUUCCAAAUUAAUUUUUAUUUUUAGCUCUAUUAGAUUUUUCUCAGUGUAACAAAUGUUUAUUCCUAUGUAAUUAAGGGUGUGUUUCCUGUACAGAAUAUUCAUAAUACCUAAUUGAAAAUUAUAUGAUACAAAAAUAUAAUACUAUUUUUAGGCCAAGCAUGGUGGCUCAUACCUGUAAUCCCAACA